AUGAGCGGGCAGGGGCUCGGGGCGCGCGGACUCCAGGCGCUGGACUGCGGCGUGGAGCAGCGCUGGGGAAACCGCGCCGGGUUCAGGGCGGGGCCUCGAGGGGCGGAGCUUGCGGUGACCAGCGAGGGGGCGGGGCUUAGAGCCACUAAGAAGCGGGACCCAGUGAGGGCUAAACGUGGGGCGCCGGGGGCGUGGCGCGGGGCGCAGGUGCACGCAGGUUGGCCGCGGGCGCGCGGGGUCCGGCGGGAGUCCCGGGGUGGUCCCCGCGUGGGGCCGGGGGCGUCCGCGCGGGCGGGGCGAGGUCGGGGAGGGCAGCUGCCCGCCCUCCUCGGCACUGGGAGCUUUCGGCUGGUACUGCGGGAGGAGCUCCCGGGUGACCCGCGGGUUCUGAAACCGCCGCUCGGGAGCUCGGGGCCUGCGCGGCGUCUACGGGGCGAGCGAGGGAGAACUGACGCCUUUCGCUCGGAUCCUUCUCCCCUUCCGAGAACCAGUGGGCUCUGCGCUCGCGUUAACAAUUCGAAUGGGCACGUUUCUGAGUUUAAGAACGCUGUUCGCUUCCUCACACUUAGAUUGAGGUGGAACUCACGUCACAUAAACCGGGUCGCAAGGCUCAGCUCAGCGGGGCCCCCCCACAGUGUUGCGGGACCAGCACCUUCUCGAGCUCCGGAACAGCUUCUACCCGCGCAGAGCCCGGCCCGUCGGCGGCCGCUCUCCGCGCCCCUCCCGGGCCCUGCAGCCCCCGCCCUGCUCCGCGGAGCAGCCUGUUCUGACCUCCGUUCCAUGGAGCCCUACGUGCUGUGGCUUCUGUGUUCCGGCGCCUUUCGCUUAGAAUCGCGUCUUAAAGGUUCGUCCGCGGUGGAGCGGGGAUCAGGCCCGUGUUCCUUUUCAGGAGUGAAUAAUAUUCCCUGGUAUGGAGACUGCGCUGAGAUAGGACCUGGGCCACCCCCUCUGAUUAUUUCCCGCCCACCCCUUCACUGGCGCCAGCCCCACGGAGACCUCGCAGGUGCCGUGAGAAAGUGGAGAUGAGCAGAGUCUGGACGCAUGCGCGGGGCCGGGAGGUGCCGGCCGCAGCCUGCGCCGUCUCCUAAUGCGGAAAUCUGCACCCAGGGCGGAACUCGCCGGUGUCUUCCGCGCGCGCACUGCACGUGUCGGCAUCCUUUCUAGUGCGCCUGCGCAGCCAGCACCGCCUGCACCUGCGCUGACGCUCGCUGACAGCAGUACCCUCCUGGGAAGCCACGCAGGACCCGUCUUCGGGAGCCCGAGAGCCUCCUUCCCGGGCGCCAGUCUUAAUAAACUUUGUAUGUGUGUGA